AAUUAGAAAUAUCAGUUAUAUUACUCAGGUUUUGAAUGGAAUGUCAUAUUUGAAAAUGACAUUCAUAGAAUCAGAUAUGAUCAGACAGUUUUAAGGAACUAUGCUGACUUUAUGAGGUCAAGGCUUACAAAAUCCUCUUGAAAAAAUUAGCCUGGUACCUGGCUUAUAGCAUGCUUAGCCUUACAGUGAGUAUAGAAGGUCACUUUCCGGUACUCUCAGGAACCAUAGGAUAUUUUGGAGACCUCAAGAAGAGAGGCAGUCAUUCAAUUCUGUUUUAAGCCCUGGAGACCCAGCUCUUCACUCUCACCUCAGAUCUGAGACGUGAUGCCACACCUUUUCCUCCAGCUGCCAUGACAAAAUACUACAGAUGGGGUAGCUUAAACACGUCGUCUGUGAGUGGGUGUUUCUCACGAUUCUGGAGGCUGCACAUCUGAGAUCAAGACGUCAGCUGCCUUGGUUUCCUCUGAAUCUUCUCCUCGGGCUGCAGAUGGACACUGUCUUGCUGCCUCUUCCUCUGGUCGUCUCUGUGCAUGCGUGCCCCCAGGGUCUCUGCGUGCCCUAAUCCCUGUUCUAAUAAGGCAUCAAUGCCUUUUAUCAGUUUAAGAGGUUACCUUCAAUACCAGGUUACUGAGGAUUUUUGUCACAAAUUUCUUCAAAUCUUUCAAAUCAGUUUUCUGAUAAUGAGGCACUGAAGAGAAUCUAGUAUGGCCAAUGUCACCUUGGUGACAGGAUUUCUUCUUAUGGGGUUUUCUAAUAUCCAGAAGCUGCGGAUUUUAUAUGGUGUGCUCUUCCUACUGAUUUACCUGGCAGCCCUAAUGAGUAACCUUCUCAUCAUUACUCUCAUUACCCUGGACGUAAAGCUCCAAACACCCAUGUACUUCUUCCUGAAGAACUUAUCCUUUUUGGAUGUCUUCCUGGUGUCUGUUCCAAUCCCAAAAUUCAUUGUCAACAACCUAACCCACAACAAUUCCAUUUCCAUUCUAGGAUGUGCCUUCCAGCUACUUUUAAUGACUUCCUUCUCAGCAGGAGAGAUAUUUAUCCUCACUGCCAUGUCCUAUGACCGCUAUGUAGCCAUCUGCUGUCCCCUGAACUACGAGGUAAUCAUGAAUACUGGAGUCUGUGUGUUAAUGGCAAGUGUUUCCUGGGCCAUUGGAGGGCUCUUUGGUACUGCGUACACAGCUGGCACAUUUUCCAUGCCUUUCUGUGGCUCCAGUGUGAUUCCACAGUUUUUCUGUGAUGUUCCUUCAUUACUAAGGAUUUCCUGUUCUGAAACACUAAUGGUAAUUUAUGCAGGUAUUGGAGUUGGUGCAUGUUUAAGCAUUUCUUGUUUCAUCUGUAUUGUGAUCUCUUACAUUUAUAUCUUCUCCACUGUACUGAAGAUCCCUACCACUAAAGGUCAGUCCAAAGCUUUUUCCACAUGCUUCCCCCAUCUCACUGUUUUCACUGUUUUUAUCAUAACUGCUUAUUUUGUUUAUCUUAAGCCACCUUCAAAUUCACCAUCUGUUAUUGACAGGCUGCUUUCUGUGAUCUACACUGUGAUGCCUCCAGUAUUUAACCCUGUAACCUACAGCCUGCGGAACAAUGACAUGAAAUGUGCUCUGAUAAGGUUGCUGCAGAAAACAUAUGGUCAGGAGGCUUACUUCAUUUAACACUUUCAAGUUCUGUCAGUGAUACAGUGCCUUACAGAUCACAAGAAACUUUCCUUAUUUGUAACUUUGGAAAGACCUGAGAAAAGAAAGCAAUAUACUCAAAUUAUUUUUUCCCUGAAGAAAUAAAUACUCAAGAGCCUAA